UACAAGUGUAAGCCACCACACCUGACCUGUUUUGUAUAUUUUACCACAAUAAAAAGCCUUUAAAACCCCAAGCAGACAGUUCAUUUUCAUUCAGGCCCAACUCAGAAUCUGAUCACAGCGGGGUUUCCCCCCUUUCUAGCGAGUAGCUGAAGAACUGUUUUCUCUCCUUGAUGGUAUAACUGUCUCUGUGGGUGUUGCUCCCCUGCCGCUCCAGUGGUUUUGUUUUUGUUUUUGUUUUUUUGAGACGGAGUCUUGCGAUCUCAGCUCACUGCGACCUCUGCCUCCUGGGUUCAGGCGAUUCUUCUCCCUCAGCCUUCCAUGUAGCUGGGACUUACAGGCACCUGCCACCACGCCCGGCUCAUUUUUGUAUUUUUAGUAGAGACGGAGUUUCACCAUGUUGGCCAGGUUGGGCUCGAACUCCAGACCUCAGGUGAUCCACCUGCCUCAGCCUCCCACAGUGCUGGGAUUACAGGUGAGAGCCACUGCACCCAGCCGGCCCCUCAGUCUUUUCCUUCUCAAUCAGUGGCACCACCAUCUUCCCAGGCUUUGGACAUGGUCCCUGACUCACCCUUGCCCCUCACCCCCACACUAAUCCACCUGCGAGCUCUGUUGCUUCACCACCUAGACCAGCCCCAAAUCCUCAACUGCCCCCACCCUGGGCCACACCUGGACCACUGCUAGAGGCCUCUCAUGGGCCCUCCCUGUUUUUCUCUUGCACUCCCCGGGCUUUCUGGCACAAGAUGCCCCAGAAGCAGAAUCACAUAUCUCUCCUGGGAGCCAAUCUAGUGUGUUUACUGCCCCUGGAGUGUUAUUGUUGGCCUUAGAAUAUGUCCCACUACAGGUUUGCAGAGCACUGUAGUCAAAAGUCAUUUGAAAUAAAUCUUUUCUCUGUGGUAUAUUGUCAAUUUGAUAUAGAAUUAAAUUUGUUUCUUUUCUUUUUUCUUUUCUUUUUUUUUUUUUUUAAGAGACAGGGUCUUGGCCAGGCGUGGUGUCUCAUGCCUGUAAUCCCGGCACUUUGGGAAGCCAAGGUGGGUGGAUCGCCUGAGGUCAGGAAUUCAAGACCAACCUGGCCAGCAUGGUGAAACCCCGUCUCUGCUAAAAAUACAAAAAUUAGCCGGGCGUGAUGGCAGGUACCUGUAAUCCCAGCUACUCGGGAAGCUGAGGCAGGAGAAGGCUUGAACUCAGGAGUCGGAGGUUGCAGUGAGCCAAGAUCACGCCAUGGCACUCUAGCAAGACUCUGUCUCAAAAAAAAAAAAAGAGAGAGAGAGAGACAGGGUCUUGCUCUGUCACUCAGGCUGGAGUGCAGUGAUGUAGUCAUGGCUCACUGCAGCCUCAUACUCCUGACCUCAGGUGAUCGACCCGCCUCGGCCUCCCAAAGUGCUGGGAUCGUAGGCUGAAGCCACCAUGCCUGGCCCGAACUCAUUUGUUUUUAUUUGCAUUAAGUGUAAUAAGGUUUUGUUACUUUUAGUUUGAAUUUUAUUUUGGGUAAUAUAAACAUUUACAUGAUUCAGAAGUCAGAAUUACACUGAGGCAUGUUCAGCUAGGCCUCACUCCUGUGCCUGUACCCUUACCUUUUUCCCCCUACCCCAUGCAGGGAAUCAAUUUCAUUAGUUCCUGGUGUGUCCUUCCUUAAUACCCCCCCUUCUUUCUUUGGUAGAAUGCAGUAGAUAUGUUUGCGCUUUGCUCCCUUUGCUUCACAGUGGAUCCUGGAAAUGACUCCAUCGCAGUUCUUAGAGCUCUUGUUUAGUCCCUUUGGAUCUGCACAGUACUCCAGUGUGUGGGCGCACCAUAAGUUUAUUCAGCAAGUGCCCUGGUGAUAGGGAUCGGGGGUAUUGGAAGCCUUUGGCUGGUAAAAAUAAUGUUGUAGCAAAUAACAUCAUGCAUAUGUUCUUUGAGAUUUCUGGAGGUGUCUCUUUAGCAUAGAUUUCUAGAAGGCAUUCCUUACGUCACGUUUAGGUUUAUAGUUUGACCUCAUGGUGAUUAAGGUAUUUGGGAAAUGCAAAUGAGAGUUUCGAAGAAGCCAGAUCUUUCCCAUUAGUUCACUGUUUUUCUCUGACAUUAGGACCGUCCGGGUUCUAGGGAGCAGCCCUGGCGUUAGGCAGUGCCAUGAUGGAUUGUGUAGAAGUAGCGAUUCCCAUCUGUCUGCUUUCUUGGCCCACUCUGCUGGUGGCUCCCCUUCCCUCCCUCCUUUAUGGGGAGCUGGGGAGCUGCCUAGGGGUCCAUUCUCAAAGGCUGAUCUCUGGUGGGCAACAGGCCACACCUAGCUUUCCAGGGUUCUUCGUCAUUUCCCAUUGAGAGCUGUAAGACUCAGAGACAUGAAAAGGAAGCUCUGGCUGGGCACGGUGGCUCACGCCUGUAAUCCCAGCACUUUGGGAGGCUGAGGCGGGUCGAUCACCUGAGGUCAGGAGUUCGAGACCAGCCUGCCCAACAUGGUGAAACCCCGUCUCCACUAAACAUACAAAAAUUAGCCUGGCGUGGUAGCACACGCCUGUGAUCCCAGCUACUCCGGAGGCUGAGGCAGGAGAAUAACUUGAACCCGGCAGGCGGAGGUUGCGAUGAGCCGAUAUUAUGCCAUCGGCAACAGAGCGAGACUCCAUCUCAAAAAAAAAACAAAAAACAAAACAAGGCGAGCUCUGUGCUGGGACAGAUUAGGGACCCCUCUUUACAGCAAGAAAGACUGCUCUGUGGGUUGUAGGAUGCCUUUGUGUAUGCAGUGGCUCUAGGUGACUCUGGCAGCCACACUCUGGGCCCUAAACUUCUGGAGGAAGAUACAGGAUAGGGAGGAACUCAGGGGUGAGUCAUGGUGGGGACAAGACAUUCCCUCACUCUAAGACCUUGUCACUAGAUUGGAACAUCUCUUGCCUCCCUACACCUGACCUGAUGGUUCUGGAGAGAUACGUCCUUGCAGCUUCUGAGUCCCAGCACUAAGCAGCCUUUGGGAAGAAAAGUCAGAAGACCAGGACCUCCAGGGCCUCAAGGACAAACCCCUCAAGUUUAAAAAGGUGAAGAAAGAUAAGAAAGAAGAGAAAGAGGGCAAGCAUGAGCCCGUGCAGCCAUCAGCCCACCACUCUGCUGAGCCCGCAGAGGCAGGCAAAGCAGAGACAUCAGAAGGGUCAGGCUCCGCCCCGGCUGUGCCGGAAGCUUCUGCCUCCCCCAAACAGCGGCGCUCCAUCAUCCGUGACCGGGGACCCAUGUAUGAUGACCCCACCCUGCCUGAAGGCUGGACACGGAAGCUUAAGCAAAGGAAAUCUGGCCGCUCUGCUGGGAAGUAUGAUGUGUAUUUGAUCAAUCCCCAGGGAAAAGCCUUUCGCUCUAAAGUGGAGUUGAUUGCGUACUUCGAAAAGGUAGGCGACACAUCCCUGGACCCUAAUGAUUUUGACUUCACGGUAACUGGGAGAGGGAGCCCCUCCCGGCGAGAGCAGAAACCACCUAAGAAGCCCAAAUCUCCCAAAGCUCCAGGAACUGGCAGAGGCCGGGGACGCCCCAAAGGGAGCGGCACCACGAGACCCAAGGCGGCCACGUCAGAGGGUGUGCAGGUGAAAAGGGUCCUGGAGAAAAGUCCUGGGAAGCUCCUUGUCAAGAUGCCUUUUCAAACUUCGCCAGGGGGCAAGGCUGAGGGGGGUGGGGCCACCACAUCCACCCAGGUCAUGGUGAUCAAACGCCCCGGCAGGAAGCGAAAAGCUGAGGCCGACCCUCAGGCCAUUCCCAAGAAACGGGGCCGAAAGCCGGGGAGUGUGGUGGCAGCCGCUGCCGCCGAGGCCAAAAAGAAAGCCGUGAAGGAGUCUUCUAUCCGAUCUGUGCAGGAGACCGUACUCCCCAUCAAGAAGCGCAAGACCCGGGAGACGGUCAGCAUCGAGGUCAAGGAAGUGGUGAAGCCCCUGCUGGUGUCCACCCUCGGUGAGAAGAGCGGGAAAGGACUGAAGACCUGUAAGAGCCCUGGGCGGAAAAGCAAGGAGAGCAGCCCCAAGGGGCGCAGCAGCAGCGCCUCCUCACCCCCCAAGAAGGAGCACCACCACCAUCACCACCACUCAGAGUCCCCAAAGGCCCCCGUGCCACUGCUCCCACCCCUGCCCCCACCUCCACCUGAGCCCGAGAGCUCCGAGGACCCCACCAGCCCCCCUGAGCCCCAGGACUUGAGCAGCAGCGUCUGCAAAGAGGAGAAGAUGCCCAGAGGAGGCUCACUGGAGAGCGACGGCUGCCCCAAGGAGCCAGCUAAGACUCAGCCCGCGGUUGCCACCGCCGCCACGGCCGCAGAAAAGUACAAACACCGAGGGGAGGGAGAGCGCAAAGACAUUGUUUCAUCCUCCAUGCCAAGGCCAAACAGAGAGGAGCCUGUGGACAGCCGGACGCCCGUGACCGAGAGAGUUAGCUGACUUUACACGGAGCGGAUUGCAAAGCAAACCAACAAGAAUAAAGGCAGCUGUUGUCUCUUCUCCUUAUGGGUAGGGCUCUGACAAAGCUUCCCGAUUAACUGAAAUAAAAAAUAUUUUUUUUUCUUUCAGUAAACUUAGAGUUUCGUGGCUUCAGGGUGGGAGUAGUUGGAGCAUUGGGGAUGUUUUUCUUACCGACAAGCACAGUCAGGUUGAAGACCUAACCAGGGCCAGAAGUAGCUUUGCACUUUUCUAAACUAGGCUCCUUCAACAAGGCUUGCUGCAGAUACUACUGACCAGACAAGCUGUUGACCAGGCACCUCCCCUCCCGCCCAAACCUUUCCCCCAUGUGGUCGUUAGAGACAGAGCGACAGAGCAGUUGAGAGGACACUCCCGUUUUCGGUGCCAUCAGUGCCCCGUCUACAGCUCCCCCAGCUCCCCCCACCUCCCCCACUCCCAACCACGUUGGGACAGGGAGGUGUGAGGCAGGAGAGACAGUUGGAUUCUUUAGAGAAGAUGGAUAUGACCAGUGGCUAUGGCCUGUGCGAUCCCACCCGUGGUGGCUCAAGUCUGGCCCCACACCAGCCCCAAUCCAAAACUGGCAAGGACGCUUCACAGGACAGGAAAGUGGCACCUGUCUGCUCCAGCUCUGGCAUGGCUAGGAGGGGGGAGUCCCUUGAACUACUGGGUGUAGACUGGCCUGAACCACAGGAGAGGAUGGCCCAGGGUGAGGUGGCAUGGUCCAUUCUCAAGGGACGUCCUCCAACGGGUGGCGCUAGAGGCCAUGGAGGCAGUAGGACAAGGUGCAGGCAGGCUGGCCUGGGGUCAGGCCGGGCAGAGCACAGCGGGGUGAGAGGGAUUCCUAAUCACUCAGAGCAGUCUGUGACUUAGUGGACAGGGGAGGGGGCAAAGGGGGAGGAGAAGAAAAUGUUCUUCCAGUUACUUUCCAAUUCUCCUUUAGGGACAGCUUAGAAUUAUUUGCACUAUUGAGUCUUCAUGUUCCCACUUCAAAACAAACAGAUGCUCUGAGAGCAAACUGGCUUGAAUUGGUGACAUUUAGUCCCUCAAGCCACCAGAUGUGACAGUGUUGAGAACUACCUGGAUUUGUAUAUAUACCUGCGCUUGUUUUAAAGUGGGCUCAGCACAUAGGGUUCCCACGAAGCUCCGAAACUCUAAGUGUUUGCUGCAAUUUUAUAAGGACUUCCUGAUUGGUUUCUCUUCUCCCCUUCCAUUUCUGCCUUUUGUUCAUUUCAUCCUUUCACUUCUUUCCCUUCCUCCAUCCUCCUCCUUCCUAGUUCAUCCCUUCUCUUCCAGGCAGCCGCGGUGCCCAACCACACUUGUCGGCUCCAGUCCCCAGAACUCUGCCUGCCCUUUGUCCUCCUGCUGCCAGUACCAGCCCCACCCUGUUUUGAGCCCUGAGGAGGCCUUGGGCUCUGCUGAGUCCGACCUGGCCUGUCUGUGAAGAGCAAGAGAGCAGCAAGGUCUUGCUCUCCUAGGUAGCCCCCUCUUCCCUGGUAAGAAAAAGCAAAAGGCAUUUCCCACCCUGAACAACGAGCCUUUUCACCCUUCUACUCUAGAGAAGUGGACUGGAGGAGCUGGGCCCGAUUUGGUAGUUGAGGAAAGCACAGAGGCCUCCUGUGGCCUGCCAGUCAUCGAGUGGCCCAACAGGGGCUCCAUGCCAGCCGACCUUGACCUCACUCAGAAGUCCAGAGUCUAGCGUAGUGCAGCAGGGCAGUAGCGGUACCAAUGCAGAACUCCCAAGACCCGAGCUGGGACCAGUACCUGGGUCCCCAGCCCUUCCUCUGCUCCCCCUUUUCCCUCGGAGUUCUUCUUGAAUGGCAAUGUUUUGCUUUUGCUCGAUGCAGACAGGGGGCCAGAACACCACACAUUUCACUGUCUGUCUGGUCCAUAGCUGUGGUGUAGGGGCUUAGAGGCAUGGGCUUGCUGUGGGUUUUUAAUUGAUCAGUUUUCAUGUGGGAUCCCAUCUUUUUAACCUCUGUUCAGGAAGUCCUUAUCUAGCUGCAUAUCUUCAUCAUAUUGGUAUAUCCUUUUCUGUGUUUACAGAGAUGUCUCUUAUAUCUAAAUCUGUCCAACUGAGAAGUACCUUAUCAAAGUAGCAAAUGAGACAGCAGUCUUAUGCUUCCAGAAACACCCACAGGCAUGUCCCAUGUGAGCUGCUGCCAUGAACUGUCAAGUGUGUGUUGUCUUGUGUAUUUCAGUUAUUGUCCCUGGCUUCCUUACUAUGGUGUAAUCAUGAAGGAGUGAAACAUCAUAGAAACUGUCUAGCACUUCCUUGCCAGUCUUUAGUGAUCAGGAACCAUAGUUGACAGUUCCAAUCAGUAGCUUAAGAAAAAACCGUGUUUGUCUCUUCUGGAAUGGUUAGAAGUGAGGGAGUUUGCCCCGUUCUGUUUGUAGAGUCUCAUAGUUGGACUUUCUAGCAUAUAUGUGUCCAUUUCCUUAUGCUGUAAAAGCAAGUCCUGCAACCAAACUCCCAUCAGCCCAAUCCCUGAUCCCUGAUCCCUUCCACCUGCUCUGCUGAUGACCCCCCCAGCUUCACUUCUGACUCUUCCCCAGGAAGGGAAGGGGGGUCAGAAGAGAGGGUGAGUCCUCCAGAACUCUUCCUCCAAGGACAGAAGGCUCCUGCCCCCAUAGUGGCCUCGAACUCCUGGCACUACCAAAGGACACUUAUCCACGAGAGCGCAGCAUCCGACCAGGUUGUCACUGAGAAGAUGUUUAUUUUGGUCAGUUGGGUUUUUAUGUAUUAUACUUAGUCAAAUGUAAUGUGGCUUCUGGAAUCAUUGUCCAGAGCUGCUUCCCCGUCACCUGGGCGUCAUCUGGUCCUGGUAAGAGGAGUGCGUGGCCCACCAGGCCCCCCUGUCACCCAUGACAGUUCAUUCAGGGCCGAUGGGGCAGUCGUGGUUGGGAACACAGCAUUUCAAGCGUCACUUUAUUUCAUUCGGGCCCCACCUGCAGCUCCCUCAAAGAGGCAGUUGCCCAGCCUCUUUCCCUUCCAGUUUAUUCCAGAGCUGCCAGUGGGGCCUGAGGCUCCUUAGGGUUUUCUCUCUAUUUCCCCCUUUCUUCCUCAUUCCCUCGUCUUUCCCAAAGGCAUCACGAGUCAGUCGCCUUUCAGCAGGCAGCCUUGGCGGUUUAUCGCCCUGGCAGGCAGGGGCCCUGCAGCUCUCAUGCUGCCCCUGCCUUGGGGUCAGGUUGACAGGAGGUUGGAGGGAAAGCCUUAAGCUGCAGGAUUCUCACCAGCUGUGUCCGGCCCAGUUUUGGGGUGUGACCUCAAUUUCAAUUUUGUCUGUACUUGAACAUUAUGAAGAUGGGGGCCUCUUUCAGUGAAUUUGUGAACAGCAGAAUUGACCGACAGCUUUCCAGUACCCAUGGGGCUAGGUCAUUAAGGCCACAUCCACAGUCUCCCCCACCCUUGUUCCAGUUGUUAGUUACUACCUCCUCUCCUGACAAUACUGUAUGUCGUCGAGCUCCCCCCAGGUCUACCCCUCCCGGCCCUGCCUGCUGGUGGGCUUGUCAUAGCCAGUGGGAUUGCCGGUCUUGACAGCUCAGUGAGCUGGAGAUACUUGGUCACAGCCAGGCGCUAGCACAGCUCCCUUCUGUUGAUGCUGUAUUCCCAUAUCAAAAGACACAGGGGACACCCAGAAACGCCACAUCCCCCAAUCCAUCAGUGCCAAACUAGCCAACGGCCCCAGCUUCUCAGCUCGCUGGAUGGCGGAAGCUGCUACUCGUGAGCGCCAGUGCGGGUGCAGACAAUCUUCUGUUGGGUGGCAUCAUUCCAGGCCCGAAGCAUGAACAGUGCACCUGGGACAGGGAGCAGCCCCAAAUUGUCACCUGCUUCUCUGCCCAGCUUUUCAUUGCUGUGACAGUGAUGGCGAAAGAGGGUAAUAACCAGACACAAACUGCCAAGUUGGGUGGAGAAAGGAGUUUCUUUAGCUGACAGAAUCUCUGAAUUUUAAAUCACUUAGUAAGCGGCUCAAGCCCAGGAGGGAGCAGAGGGAUACGAGCGGAGUCCCCUGCGCGGGACCAUCUGGAAUUGGUUUAGCCCAAGUGGAGCCUGACAGCCAGAACUCUGUGUCCCCCGUCUAACCACAGCUCCUUUUCCAGAGCAUUCCAGUCAGGCUCUCUGGGCUGACUGGGCCAGGGGAGGUUACAGGUACCAGUUCUUUAAGAAGAUCUUUGGGCAUAUACAUUUUUAGCCUGUGUCAUUGCCCCAAAUGGAUUCCUGUUUCAAGUUCACACCUGCAGAUUCUAGGACCUGUGUCCUAGACUUCAGGGAGUCAGCUGUUUCUAGAGUUCCUACCAUGGAGUGGGUCUGGAGGACCUGCCCGGUGGGGGGGCAGAGCCCUGCUCCCUCCGGGUCUUCCUACUCUUCUCUCUGCUCUGACGGGAUUUGUUGAUUCUCUCCAUUUUGGUGUCUUUCUCUUUUAGAUAUUGUAUCAAUCUUUAGAAAAGGCAUAGUCUACUUGUUAUAAAUCGUUAGGAUACUGCCUCCCCCAGGGUCUAAAAUUACAUAUUAGAGGGGAAAAGCUGAACACUGAAGUCAGUUCUCAACAAUUUAGAAGGAAAACCUAGAAAACAUUUGGCAGAAAAUUACAUUUCGAUGUUUUUGAAUGAAUACGAGCAAGCUUUUACAACAGUGCUGAUCUAAAAAUACUUAGCACUUGGCCUGAGAUGCCUGGUGAGCAUUACAGGCAAGGGGAAUCUGGAGGUAGCCGACCUGAGGACAUGGCUUCUGAACCUGUCUUUUGGGAGUGGUAUGGAAGGUGGAGCGUUCACCAGUGACCUGGAAGGCCCAGCACCACCCUCCUUCCCACUCUUCUCAUCUUGACAGAGCCUGCCCCAGCGCUGACGUGUCAGGAAAACACCCAGGGAACUAGGAAGGCACUUCUGCCUGAGGGGCAGCCUGCCUUGCCCACUCCUGCUCUGCUCGCCUCGGAUCAGCUGAGCCUUCUGAGCUGGCCUCUCACUGCCUCCCCAAGGCCCCCUGCCUGCCCUGUCAGGAGGCAGAAGGAAGCAGGUGUGAGGGCAGUGCAAGGAGGGAGCACAACCCCCAGCUCCCGCUCCGGGCUCCGACUUGUGCACAGGCAGAGCCCAGACCCUGGAGGAAAUCCUACCUUUGAAUUCAAGAACAUUUGGGGAAUUUGGAAAUCUCUUUGCCCCCAAACCCCCAUUCUGUCCUACCUUUAAUCAGGUCCUGCUCAGCAGUGAGAGCAGAUGAGGUGAAAAGGCCAAGAGGUUUGGCUCCUGCCCACUGAUAGCCCCUCUCCCCGCAGUGUUUGUGUGUCAAGUGGCAAAGCUGUUCUUCCUGGUGACCCUGAUUAUAUCCAGUAACACAUAGACUGUGCGCAUAGGCCUGCUUUGUCUCCUCUAUCCUGGGCUUUUGUUUUGCUUUUUAGUUUUGCUUUUAGUUUUUCUGUCCCUUUUAUUUAACGCACCGACUAGACACACAAAGCAGUUGAAUUUUUAUAUAUAUAUCUGUAUAUUGCACAAUUAUAAACUCAUUUUGCUUGUGGCUCCACACACACAAAAAAAGACCUGUUAAAAUUAUACCUGUUGCUUAAUUACAAUAUUUCUGAUAACCAUAGCAUAGGACAAGGGAAAAUAAAAAAAGAAAAAAAAGAAAAAAAAACGACAAAUCUGUCUGCUGGUCACUUCUUCUGUCCAAGCAGAUUCGUGGUCUUUUCCUCGCUUCUUUCAAGGGCUUUCCUGUGCCAGGUGAAGGAGGCUCCAGGCAGCACCCAGGUUUUGCACUCUUGUUUCUCCCGUGCUUGUGAAAGAGGUCCCAAGGUUCUGGGUGCAGGAGCGCUCCCUUGACCUGCUGAAGUCCGGAACGUAGUCGGCACAGCCUGGUCGCCUUCCACCUCUGGGAGCUGGAGUCCACUGGGGUGGCCUGACUCCCCCAGUCCCCUUCCCGUGACCUGGUCAGGGUGAGCCCAUGUGGAGUCAGCCUCGCAGGCCUCCCUGCCAGUAGGGUCCGAGUGUGUUUCAUCCUUCCCACUCUGUCGAGCCUGGGGGCUGGAGCGGAGACGGGAGGCCUGGCCUGUCUCGGAACCUGUGAGCUGCACCAGGUAGAACGCCAGGGACCCCAGAAUCAUGUGCGUCAGUCCAAGGGGUCCCCUCCAGGAGUAGUGAAGACUCCAGAAAUGUCCCUUUCUUCUCCCCCAUCCUACGAGUAAUUGCAUUUGCUUUUGUAAUUCUUAAUGAGCAAUAUCUGCUAGAGAGUUUAGCUGUAACAGUUCUUUUUGAUCAUCUUUUUUUAAUAAUUAGAAACACCAAAAAAAUCCAGAAACUUGUUCUUCCAAAGCAGAGAGCAUUAUAAUCACCAGGGCCAAAAGCUUCCCUCCCUGCUGUCAUUGCUUCUUCUGAGGCCUGAAUCCAAAAGAAAAACAGCCAUAGGCCCUUUCAGUGGCCGGGCUACCCGUGAGCCCUUCGGAGGACCAGGGCUGGGGCAGCCUCUGGGCCCACAUCCGGGGCCAGCUCCGGCGUGUGUUCAGUGUUAGCAGUGGGUCAUGAUGCUCUUUCCCACCCAGCCUGGGAUAGGGGCAGAGGAGGCGAGGAGGCCGUUGCCGCUGAUGUUUGGCCGUGAACAGGUGGGUGUCUGCGUGCGUCCACGUGCGUGUUUUCUGACUGACAUGAAAUCGACGCCCGAGUUAGCCUCACCCGGUGACCUCUAGCCCUGCCCGGAUGGAGCGGGGCCCACCCGGUUCAGUGUUUCUGGGGAGCUGGACAGUGGAGUGCAAAAGGCUUGCAGAACUUGAAGCCUGCUCCUUCCCUUGCUACCACGGCCUCCUUUCCGUUUGAUUUGUCACUGCUUCAAUCAAUAACAGCCGCUCCAGAGUCAGUAGUCAAUGAAUAUAUGACCAAAUAUCACCAGGACUGUUACUCAAUGUGUGCCGAGCCCUUGCCCAUGCUGGGCUCCCGUGUAUCUGGACACUGUAACGUGUGCUGUGUUUGCUCCCCUUCCCCUUCCUUCUUUGCCCUUUACUUGUCUUUCUGGGGUUUUUCUGUUUGGGUUUGGUUUGGUUUUUAUUUCUCCUUUUGUGUUCCAAACAUGAGGUUCUCUCUACUGGUCCUCUUAACUGUGGUGUUGAGGCUUAUAUUUGUGUAAUUUUUGGUGGGUGAAAGGAAUUUUGCUAAGUAAAUCUCUUCUGUGUUUGAACUGAAGUCUGUAUUGUAACUAUGUUUAAAGUAAUUGUUCCAGAGACAAAUAUUUCUAGACACUUUUUCUUUACAAACAAAAGCAUUCGGAGGGAGGGGGAUGGUGACUGAGAUGAGAGGGGAGAGCUGAACAGAUGACCCCUGCCCAGAUCAGCCAGAAGCCACCCAAAGCAGUGGAGCCCAGGAGUCCCACUCCAAGCCAGCAAGCCGAAUAGCUGAUGUGUUGCCACUUUCCAAGUCACUGCAAAACCAGGUUUUGUUCCGCCCAGUGGAUUCUUGUUUUGCUUCCCCUCCCCCCGAGAUUAUUACCACCAUCCCGUGCUUUUAAGGAAAGGCAAGAUUGAUGUUUCCUUGAGGGGAGCCAGGAGGGGAUGUGUGUGUGCAGAGCUGAAGAGCUGGGGAGAAUGGGGCUGGGCCCACCCAAGCAGGAGGCUGGGACGCUCUGCUGUGGGCACAGGUCAGGCUAAUGUUGGCAGAUGCAGCUCUUCCUGGACAGGCCAGGUGGUGGGCAUUCUCUCUCCAAGGUGUGCCCCGUGGGCAUUACUGUUUAAGACACUUCCGUCACAUCCCACCCCAUCCUCCAGGGCUCAACACUGUGACAUCUCUAUUCCCCACCCUCCCCUUCCCAGGGCAAUAAAAUGACCAUGGAGGGGGCUUGCACUCUCUUGGCUGUCACCCGAUCGCCAGCAAAACUUAGAUGUGAGAAAACCCCUUCCCAUUCCAUGGCGAAAACAUCUCCUUAGAAAAGCCAUUACCCUCAUUAGGCAUGGUUUUGGGCUCCCAAAACACCUGACAGCCCCUCCCUCCUCUGAGAGGCGGAGAGUGCUGACUGUAGUGACCAUUGCAUGCCGGGUGCAGCAUCUGGAAGAGCUAGGCAGGGUGUCUGCCCCCUCCUGAGUUGAAGUCAUGCUCCCCUGUGCCAGCCCAGAGGCCGAGAGCUAUGGACAGCAUUGCCAGUAACACAGGCCACCCUGUGCAGAAGGGAGCUGGCUCCAGCCUGGAAACCUGUCUGAGGUUGGGAGAGGUGCACUUGGGGCACAGGGAGAGGCCGGGACACACUUAGCUGGAGAUGUCUCUAAAAGCCCUGUAUCGUAUUCACCUUCAGUUUUUGUGUUUUGGGACAAUUACUUUAGAAAAUAAGUAGGUCGUUUUAAAAACAAAAAUUAUUGAUUGCUUUUUUGUAGUGUUCAGAAAAAAGGUUCUUUGUGUAUAGCCAAAUGACUGAAAGCACUGAUAUAUUUAAAAACAAAAGGCAAUUUAUUAAGGAAAUUUGUACCAUUUCAGUAAACCUGUCUGAAUGUACCUGUAUACGUUUCAAAAACACCCCCCCCCCACUGAAUCCCUGUAACCUAUUUAUUAUAUAAAGAGUUUGCCUUAUAAAUUUACAUAAAAAUGUCCGUUUGUGUCUUUUGUUGUAAAAAUCAAGUGAUUUUUUCAUAAGGUUCUUUUACUAUUGGAAAAGAUGGGCAGCACGCAGUUUUAUUUUAUUUUUGUAAGUUUUUUAAUACAUGUGAAAGCAAAGAAUACUCAGCAUGCCUUUCUAAGUGACGCGUUUGCACCUUUUGUUGGGAAGUACUGUAUCCUGUGCUGUUAGCAUUCUCGAUAAAUCUCUCUGUGAAAGUGA